GCUGACCAUGCUGGAACUGCGGCGACUACAGAGCCUGCGGGAACCUCCCCUUUCGCCCAAGAUCUGCUCUGUCCCCCUCAUCCUCCUCCCAGGGCCCUGGCGUCUGGGUCAAGCAGCGCCCCACACCUCGACCCCUCACCCCCUCCUCCCGGGCUCUUCCUGCGGCCUCCCCUCCACAGUCCGCAGGCUCUGGGACAGGACCGAGUCCUUGGCUGCCUGUGGAGCUCCUGUGCCAGCAGCUGCGCCCCGGCUGCGCUCCGGAUACCCCCAUCCCCGCCACCGCCGACCUCCCGCUCCACCGACUGCUGCUCACGCCCGACGGGUUCACGCCGCCCCUGCCCCGUGAAGGACCGCGCUGCGGUGCGGAGGCAGGAUGACGCAAAACACGGUGAUUGUGAAUGGAGUUGCUAUGGCCUCUAGGCCAUCCCAGCCCACCCACGUCAACGUCCACAUCCACCAGGAGUCAGCUUUGACACAACUGCUGAAAGCUGGAGGUUCUCUGAAGAAGUUUCUUUUUCACCCUGGGGACACUGUGCCUUCCACAGCCAGGAUUGGUUAUGAGCAGCUGGCUCUAGGGGUGACUCAGAUAUUGCUGGGGGUUGUGAGUUGUGUUCUUGGAGUGUGUCUCAGCUUGGGGCCCUGGACUGUGCUGAGUGCCUCAGGCUGUGCCUUCUGGGCGGGGUCUGUGGUGAUCGCAGCAGGAGCUGGGGCCAUUGUCCAUGAGAAGCACCCGGGCAAACUUGCUGGCUAUAUAUCCAGCCUGCUCACCCUGGCAGGCUUUGCUACAGCUAUGGCUGCUGUUGUCCUCUGCGUGAAUAGCUUCAUCUGGCAAACUGAACCCUUUUUAUACAUCGACACUGUGUGUGAUCGCUCAGACCCUGUCUUCCCUACCACUGGGUACAGAUGGAUGCGGCGAAGUCAAGAGAACCAAUGGCAGAAGGAGGAGUGUAGAGCUUACAUGCAGAUGCUGAGGAAGUUGUUCACAGCAAUCCGUGCCCUGUUCCUGGCUGUCUGUGUCUUGAAGGUCAUUGUGUCCUUGGUUUCCUUGGGAGUAGGUCUUCGAAACUUGUGUGGCCAGAGCUCCCAGCCCCUGAAUGAGGAAGGAUCAGAGAAGAGGCUACUGGGGGAGAAUUCAGUGCCCCCUUCGCCCUCUAGGGAGCAGACCUCCACUGCCAUUGUCCUGUGAGCUGCCAAAGACCCCACGGGGUGCCCGCAUGUCCCUGUCUAGGGCAGCCCAGGGCCCCCACUCCUGGCUCCUCACACUUGCCUCCCCUAUGGCCGCUCUCCAGACCCUCCUCCUUUCUUCUCCCCACAUCCGCACCUGCUGUUCCCACUCUGGGGUUCUCAAGUCCAUGAACAGAUAUUGUUGCAUUUUCCACAAUGCUGAUUAAACAUAAUAAACAAUCCAGAAAAGCA